AGAUUUAGUUUGUCUCUGGAAAGGCACACUUGAGUGACUGUGUAUCCUUUUGUGUUGCUUUGAUAACAUUUGUCAUAUAUGUCUCAAUUAGUAGCAUUUAGGAAACCAAUAUGUGGACCAAAUUUUCAGGCCUUGUUUAAUUAUAAGGCUUUUCUCUUCUAGGCAAGAGUCACCUUGUGGUUAGAGAAAAGAACUGAUAAGAGCAGAUGUCAUGCUGGAGCCAGGGCAAUGGCCGGUCUUUGAGAAAUAGGAAGAUCCAAAAACUAGCUGGCUUAGGCCAAAGGUGUGGGCAGUGAGCAGGGGAUAGGCAGGAGUUGCAUGGCACACAGACCCUGAGUCUGGACAGGAGGGUCUGUAAGUAGGUGAACAGGCAGCAUCUAAAAAUGCCUGAGCCAAGGGGCGAAACAGGGAUCACAGGCUAGAGAUGUCUCAGAACAUUUUUGGAAGUAAGCAAGAUAUAUACAUUAUAAUUAUAUCAUAAUUAAAUAAUAGAGGUCAUAGGAUGAAGACAGUGCCAGAGGUCCAAGCAGCCAGUCUGGAUCAGCACAAAGCAGUAAGCUAGGAAAUUGUCAGCUGGCACCGUGGAGCAUCAUGAGCACAAAAACCCAUGCUCCUCUCUGUGCAGGAAGCAGCCUGUCUGUAGAUAAACCAGGGAAGCUGUGGUACUUGGCUACAAGUGAGAGAGAAGGAGGUAGCAGUUGAAGUAAGUCUCUGCCAUCAGUUUUUCUUUGCCUUGAAUGCUUAUUCCAUGAGUUUUAGCAGUUUAAUCCUUGGAGAGUGCAGAGCUGCGUGGCAGUGAAGCAGUCCUUGUUGAGCUAUGGCAUGUUCUAAUUUAGCAAGAAAGAUUGCAGCACUUGGUGUGUAUAGGGUUAUGUUUUAUGGGAGUCUGAAAGUGAUAUGUAUAAAAACUCAUCUAUGAUUUUUUAUACAUCUACGUAAUCUGUGAUUAUCUUGGCUUGAUAGUUUGCUAUUUAUCAGUAAGGGUCAAGUAUCAGUUAAUUUUUUCCUUUUUUGUGAAGGUAAGUGAGCAAGAAAUUGUUAUUUAGUGAAACAUUGAUUUAUUUGGCAUUACAAAUUCCAUGAACAAUCCACUUUAUCUCUGCAUAAUGUGUCUUUGCUACAGGUUGAAAUCAGUUGCUUAUGUGUCUCAUGUCUUAAGCAGGAAUGAUACAAUACAUUGACAGCUCAAAUGGCCUCUUAUUUCAGUAACCAGAGCACCAUAAAACCUAAUUCCAACUGCUUAAAAAAAAACCUGAAAUAUUUCAGACCUACCUUCAAAGUAACCCCUACCCAGAAUUUGUGUUCAUCCUUUGUGUUAGUUUUCUGCUACUGCAUAUUACAGAUUACAACAAAUGUAGCAGCUUGAAACAUUACACAUUUUGUCAUCCACAGUUUCUGUGGGUUGGAAAACCAGACAUGGCUUAGCCACAUCUUCUCCUUAGGGUCUCACAAAGCCACAAUCAGAAUGUUGGCCAGGGUGCAUUCUCAUCUGGAGGACUGACUGAUGAAGAACCUGCUUCCAAGCUCACUAAAGGUUGUUGAUAGAAUUCAUAUAUUUGCACCUGCAGUACUAAGAGUCCCAGAUUUUUUCUGGCCUUUGGCUGCCCUCAGCUCCUAGAGGCCACCUACAGUUUCUUGUCAUAUGGACCUUCCCAACUUGGAGGCCCUCUUCAUCAAGCCAUAUAAGAGAGUAGAAGGAAUCUCCUAGCAAGACAGAGUCCUGUAUGAUGGUAUAGAAUCACAGUGUGACAUCUCAUCACUUUUGCCAUAUUCCGUUUGUUAGAAGAAGCAAGUCACAGGUCCCACUCACACUCGAGAAGGAGAUUUCUAAACAAAGGUGUGAACACUGGGAAGCAGGCAUCAUGGGAGGGGCACUUUUAGUCUGUCUGCCACAUCCUUCUCUUGCUUUUCUUUAUAGUUUUACAACCUGUGUACGUAUUUCUAAAGAAUAUUGUCACAUUUGCAUGCUUUUGAAACUUUGUAUAAAUGGAAUUUCAUUGUAGUUAUUCUACAACCUGCCUUUUUUUUUUUAACUUUGUGAGAUUAAUCUAUGUUAAUGCCUAUUCCCGUAGCUCGUUUAUUGUUCAGUGUGGCAUAGGAUUCCUUUACUUAAAUGUACAUUUUAUUUAUACAGUGUUUUGGUCACUAUAUAUUUGCUGUUUUCGUUUUUUUUUUUUUUUUUUUUUUCAAAUCUAAUCAAUGCUACCUUGAUUAUUUUUGUAUAUAUCUCCUUAUGCACUUUUACAAGAAAUUCUAGGGAAUAUACCUAUAGUGGAGUUGCCUUGGUAAUCUCUUGCUUAACAAGAUAAUUCCAAUUUAUUGUCCAAAGUAGUUCUGAUUUACACUCCCAAUAGGAGUGUUUAACAGUUACAGUUGUUCCACAUGCUCACCAAAAUUUGGUUUUGUUAGGCUUUUGAUUUGUGCCAGUCUGAUGGGUAUAUUACGGUAUUUUGCAGUUUUAGUUUACAUUUUCUUUAUAACUCUUUUAAUGUGUUUAUUGGUCAAUCUUGUGUUCUCGUGUGAAGAUAUUAAUAGUUCUUGGAGUCAUUUCCCUGUUUUUCUAUUAUGGUACUUUAUUGUUUUAAAUACUGCUUUUCAGAUGUCCUUUGUAUAUUCUGGAUACUAAUUCCUUGUCAGUUUUGAAUUUUGCAAAUUUCUUCUCCAGUGUAGAACUUGUUUUUACUUUCCAUUUGGUACCUUUUAAUAGGCAGAAGUUAUUAAUGUAAAUGUACUCGAAUUAUCAUUAUUUUAUGGGUUUUGCUUUUUGUAUCCUAAGAAAAUUGAAAUUAAGUCUAUGUUGAAGUCACAAAACUCUCUUAUGUUUUCUUCUAAAUUUUAAUAUUUUACUUUUCAUGUUUAAAUAUUUAAUUCAUUGUUUGCAAAGAAGGCAUCCAGGUUCAUUUUUUCCUCAUUUAAAUGUCCAGCUGUUCCAACAUUAUUGAAUAGUCCAUCUUUAUCCACUGAUUAGCUUUGUCCACUCUGUCAGAAAUCAGAUUAUUACCUAUGUACAUAGGUCUGUUUCUGGACUAAUUUUAUUUUUUUCUGGUUGUCUCUAACUAUCUCUAUUCAGUGCUGUCUUCAUUUUUAAAUGUUUUGACAUCAAAAAGACCAAAUCCCUUUACCGUGUUUUUCUUUGUUAGUGUCUUGUUUGUUCCUAUUUGCUCCUAUAUAUCAAGUUUAUGGUCAGCUUGUCAGCUUCUAUGAAAAGCCCUGUUGAGGCUUCGAUUGGAAUUACUUUAUGUCCAUACACCUAUUUGGCAUGAAUCAGCAUUUUAUAAUACAGCAUCUUUCCAUCCAUGAAUGUAUUAGGUUUAUUUAUCUAUUUAUUUAGGUCAUUUUAAAUGUUUUUCAUGAAGUUUUAUAGUUUUAUUUAUAAAGAGUUUUGAUCACUUGUUAGAUUUUGUUGCUAUUCUAAAAAUCAUUUUAAAUACACAUAUUUUCUAUUUAUUGCUAUUCUAUUUAUGCAUUUUCUAUUCCUAAUUAUAGAAGUAUAAUUAACUUUUGUAUAUUGAUCUUGCAUUUUUGCCACCUUGCUAAGCUGUCUCACUAAUUAUAAUUUAUCCGUAGCUUGUUUUAAGUGGACAGUCAUAUUGUGUAGAUAAUUCCAUUUCUUUCUAUUCAGUUCUUAUAAUUUUUCUAUCUCUCCAGCCCAUCUUUAGAGCUACUUUGAGAGUUGUCAUUUUAGCAGAACACAUACAUUUAGAUGUAACAUGUGCCUGAAAGGUCAUCAUUUUCAUGAAAUUUCUAGAGUCUACCCUAGCACAGGGGCCUCUCCUUCCUCUGAACCUUUAUGAAUUUACUUGCCUAUACUACCUUUUUGUUGGUCACCCUAUGCUUGUGAUGUUAAUCUCUUUGUUUAUGUUGUAUCUCAGCCAUUUUUUUCCCUUCAUAGCAUUAGGGCAGCACCCCAGGCCUAUGAGCACCAAAGAUUGGUUGGUUGGUUAAUUGAAAUGCCUUCUGGAUACUUGCAUUUAUAUGGUACCAUUAGGCUUCUCAGCUCCACCAGAUGGCCUCCCCCAAGUCCCCCACAUGGCAUACUGUGCUCUGGAAAACCUGUAUCUUCUGAUGGGAAGGGAACUGGAAUAUCUAGAGGAGGUACCUCCAGGAAAUGUGCUAGGAAUAGGAGGCCUUCAAGAUUUUGUGCUGAAAUCUGCAACACUGUGUAGCCUGCCAUCCUGCCCACCAUUUAUACCACUCAACUUCGAAGCCACUCCUAUUGUGAGAGUUGCUGUUGAACCAAAACAUCCAAGUGAAAUGCCUCAGCUCGUAAAAGGAAUGAAACUGUUAAACCAGGCUGAUCCCUGUGUCCAGAUUUUAAUUCAGGAAACGGGAGAGCACGUUUUAGUCACAGCAGGAGAAGUCCACCUUCAGCGAUGCCUGGAUGACUUAAAAGAAAGGUUUGCAAAGAUUCAUAUCAGUGUAUCUGAACCUAUUAUUCCAUUCAGAGAAACAAUCACAAAACCCCCAAAAGUUGACAUGGUCAAUGAAGAAAUAGGCAAACAGCAAAAAGUUGCAGUCAUACACCAAAUGAAAGAAGAUCAAAGCAAAAUCCCUGAAGGAAUCCAAGUUGACUCUGACGGGCUAAUCACCAUAACAACUCCCAAUAAACUUGCCACGCUCAGUGUUCGAGCCAUGCCCCUUCCAGAAGAAGUCACCCAGAUUCUGGAAGAAAAUAGUGAUUUGAUUCGUUCUAUGGAGCAGUUGACAUCCUCUUUGAAUGAGGGUGAAAAUACUCACAUGAUUCAUCAGAAGACCCAAGAGAAAAUUUGGGAAUUCAAAGGAAAACUGGAGCAACACCUAACAGGGAGAAGAUGGAGGAACAUUGUUGACCAAAUCUGGUCAUUUGGCCCAAGAAAAUGUGGGCCCAACAUACUAGUCAAUAAAAGUGAAGAUUUUCAGAACUCAGUAUGGACAGGUCCAGCUGACAAAGCUUCAAAAGAAGCCAGUAGAUACCGAGAUUUGGGCAAUAGCAUUGUGAGUGGCUUCCAACUAGCAACCCUCUCUGGCCCCAUGUGUGAGGAGCCUCUCAUGGGUGUCUGUUUUGUUCUGGAAAAAUGGGACCUAAGUAAAUUUGAGGAACAAGGAGCAAGUGAUCUGGCAAAAGAGGGACAGGAGGAAAAUGAAACCUGUUCUGGUGGAAAUGAAAACCAAGAGCUACAAGAUGGCUGCUCUGAGGCCUUUGAGAAGAGGACAUCACAGAAAGGAGAAUCUCCACUCACUGACUGCUAUGGACCUUUCUCAGGACAGCUAAUUGCCACCAUGAAAGAAGCAUGUCGCUAUGCACUGCAAGUGAAACCUCAGCGCCUGAUGGCAGCUAUGUACACAUGUGACAUCAUGGCCACUGGUGAUGUUCUCGGUCGAGUCUAUGCUGUCUUGUCAAAGAGAGAAGGUCGGGUACUUCAAGAAGAAAUGAAAGAAGGGACAGACAUGUUCAUCAUCAAGGCUGUGCUGCCUGUUGCUGAAAGCUUUGGUUUUGCUGAUGAAAUCAGGAAGAGGACAAGUGGCCUGGCCAGCCCACAACUAGUAUUCAGCCAUUGGGAGAUCAUUCCCAGUGACCCCUUCUGGGUGCCAACUACUGAGGAGGAAUACUUGCACUUUGGGGAGAAGGCUGACUCUGAGAACCAAGCCCGGAAGUACAUGAACGCAGUACGAAAGCGGAAGGGGCUUUAUGUGGAAGAAAAGAUUGUGGAGCAUGCAGAAAAGCAGAGGACACUCAGCAAAAAUAAGUAGCUACCUACUACUGGUGGAUUCUUUUCCUUAUAGUGAAUUUAAAAGUAUCAUCAAGGGUUUAAUAUUGGGAAAAUUUCUUUUUGCCACAUUAUCUCUGUUUAUUCACUUUCAAUAAAGUUGAUCCAUAUAAAUAUUUUAAA